AGGCCAACUGUGACGACUCUACACAAGACAUCAAGGCGGACCAGGAUUGGAGCAGAAGUCCAGACACCUAGCUUAAAUGGAGUCAGAAAGAACCACUAGUCAAGGCAUACAAGAAAGAAACUUAAUAAGAGUGUGAGCAGCUGCAUAGUACACACAGCCUUGGAGAAAGAAGCCCCUCAAUGGAACAUGAUGGAACUUUGAGUGAGUACAAAAGUAGAGACAUGAGCUUAAGGACUUGAUUUAUGAGAUCUGACAUCAACUUAAACCACACAGCAUGGAAACUAAGAUGAAGACCAGAAGAAGCCUUUCCAAAGCACUUUCACAAUUAUAAUUCAACAAUCAACUGUUUAGAUCUGAUUUUCCCAGUAAAAUAUAAACUCUGGGAAGACAGGAACUUUGCCUGCCUUCUUCAAUUUGAUCACUUCAUCACCUAAACAAAGCAUACAGACUUCUAUUUGGUUGGUUAUUAAUUAAUUAAUAAUCAAUAUUUGACAAAUUUUGCGUUCACAUGGCAAAAGUCAAUACCAUAGCCCCUCAUCAGUCCUCUACAGUUGGUUGUAAAUAAUUCUGCUUAUAUUACCUACAGAGUAAACAUUAUAGCAUUAUCACUCCAGAAUCCUUUGUUUCUAUGGUUUCCAGAUGUUUCCAAUGUCUAGAUGUUCCAGCUGCCCAUCUCUGAGAAAUCCAGCUGUGUCUCACAAUGGAUGCCACAGCCUGUAAUGAAUCAGUGGAUGGCUCACCCGUCUUCUAUCUAUUGGGCAUCCCCUCUCUGCCAGAGACCUUCUUCCUCCCUGUGUUUUUUAUUUUCCUCCUCUUCUACCUUCUCAUCCUGAUGGGUAAUGCCCUGAUCCUGGUGGCCGUGGUGGCAGAGCCCAGCCUCCACAAGCCCAUGUACUUCUUUCUGAUCAAUCUCUCCACCUUGGACAUCCUUUUCACCACAACCACUGUCCCCAAGAUGCUGUCCUUAUUCUUGCUUGGGGACCGCUUCCUCAGCUUUUCUUCCUGCUUACUGCAGAUGUACCUCUUCCAAAGUUUUACAUGUUCAGAAGCCUUCAUCCUGGUGGUCAUGGCCUAUGACCGCUAUGUGGCUAUCUGCCACCCACUGCACUACCCUGUCCUCAUGAACCCACAGACCAAUGCUACCUUGGCAGCCAGUGCCUGGCUAACUGCCCUCCUCCUGCCCAUCCCAGCAGUAGUAAGGACCUCCCAGAUGGCAUAUAACAGCAUUGCCUACAUCUACCACUGCUUCUGUGAUCAUCUGGCUGUGGUCCAGGCCUCCUGCUCUGACACCACCCCCCAGACCCUCAUGGGCUUCUGCAUCGCCAUGGUGGUGUCCUUCCUCCCCCUUCUCCUGGUGCUUCUCUCCUAUGUCCACAUCCUGGCCUCAGUGCUUCGCAUCAGUUCCCUAGAAGGACGGGCAAAAGCCUUCUCCACCUGCAGCUCCCACCUUCUGGUCGUGGGCACCUACUACUCAUCUAUUGCCAUAGCCUACGUGGCCUACAGGGCUGACCUGCCCCUUGACUUCCAUAUCAUGGGCAAUGUGGUAUAUGCCAUUCUCACACCAAUUCUCAACCCCCUCAUUUACACGCUGAGAAACAGGGAUGUAAAGGCAGCCAUCACCAAAAUCAUGUCUCAAGACCCAGGCUGUGACAGGAGCAUUUGACCUUUAAAUGCAGCUAACUCUGCUUCCAGGACACCAAAUAACAGUGCUUAGCACAGAGAAAGGACUCAAUACAUGAUAAUGAAAUAAUGUUAAUUUUUAUUGGAAUCUUAAGUUGUUGUAUAAAAUUUUACUACUUAGUAAUUCAAGAAACCUUUACUAAAAUAAAAAAAAAAUCUUCAUGGCAAAAAAUUCUUAAAAGCAAAGUCAAAAAACAAAUAAAAAACGUAUCACAGGGAAAGGCAAAUAUUCAUAUUAUACAAAGAAUGUAGAAGAUUGAAAUAAACAUUUCAAUAAAAACAUGGGCAAAAUAUAUGUGUAGACAAAUAAAAAAAAAUGCAGUGGCCUUUAAAUAAUGAGUAUUUACUAUAUAAAAAGAAUACGAAUUUAAAUUGUGCUGAAAUGUUAUUUUUCACUUAAUCAGAUUAGCAGAUUAGCAAAAAUCCAAUAUUUUGACAAUAUGCAUGUAGAAAAACAGAACUUUUAUAACUUGCUUGUGAGGAUGCAAACUGGUAUAACACUACCGCAAUACCUACCAAAAUUACAUAUGCAUUUACCCUUUGACUCAGCAGUAUCACUUCUAGGGAUCUAUCCCGAGGAGUCACCAUCAAUCAUUCAUUAGGUUACGUAUUCAUCACUAUACAGGGAACUGAUUGAAUAAACCAUAAAAAUGCAUGAUGCAGUAAUAAAAAGGAAAUAAGGAAGCUCUCUACUGAUAUGAUAUCAUCUCUAGGAUAUGUGUUAAGUGAAAAAAAGCAAGCUGCAGAAAAGUGUUUUUGUAAGAAAGGAGAUAGUUUGCUUAAAAUUUCAGGAAAAAACUAGAGGGAAAAUGUGAACUCAUAAAGAUGGUUAUCUAUAAGGAGAGGCAAGGAACAGGAAGGAGAGGACCAGAAUGGAAGCAAGUCUAGACAUAUGUAAUUAUUUUUACAUAGUUCAAAGAAAUCAGAAAGAAAAACCCCACAAUUCCCUCAAUUUAAAAUAAACAGAAGCACUUGACCCUGGCUGUCUCUCAAGUUAGUGGCAUGACCACAAAGAAAAUUACUGUAAGUGACUUUUACACAAUGUUUUGACUAUACAUCCUAAAAGGGAUGUAUUAAAAGGACAAGAAAAAUCACAUCUUAAACUACAUUGAGGAGUUUUUGUUGUUGUUGUUGUUUGUCUGUUCUGAGAAGAGGCCUUGCUCUGUCACCCAGGCUGGAGUGCAGUGGCGCUAUCUCGGCUCAUUGCAGCCUUGACCGCUAGGGCUCAAGUGAUCCUCCCACCUCAGCUCCCUGAGUAGCUGGGACCACAGGCACAUGCACCACUACCCCCAGCUAGAGUAGUUUUAAAAACAUGAAUAUUAUAGUUUUACUUCUUUAAUAUAUAUUAGAUAAAUUAUAUGUUCGUAUAACCAAAACCAUUUUUAUCAUUUUAUUUUACCAUGCAUGGUUUUAUAUUUACAGAGAGUUUCAAAGAUAGUAUGAGAGUUCCCAUAUAUCCUUCACCUAACUUCCUCUGUGUCAACAUCUUACAUAACCAUGAUACAUUUAUCAAAAGUAAGAAGUUAACAUUUGUAAAAUACGUACUAUUAAUUAUACUAGAGACUUUAUUCAAAUUUCUCCAGUUUUUCCAGUAAUGUCUUCUUUCCAUUCCAGGAUCCAAUCAGAAUGCCACAUUGCAUUUUAUUAUAUCUUCUUAGUUGCCUGACAUUUUAUUGGUCUUUCCUUAUCUUUCAUGACCUUGACACUUUUGAAGAGUCAAUAGUAAAUUUAAAUGCAUAUGGCUAAGUGAAAGAAGCCAAUCUAAAAAGGUUACAUAAUGUAUGAUUUUAACUGUAUGACAUUCUGGAAAAGGCAAAACUAUGAAGACAGUAAAGAGCUCAGGGGCUGCCAGGGAGACUAGGAGAAGGGAGGGAUUAAUAGGCAGAACACGGAGGGCUUUUAGGACAGUGAAACUAUUCUGUAUGAUACUAUAAUGGUGGAUACAUGUUAUAUAUUUGUCAAGACUCAUAGAAUGUACUACACCAAGUGUAUACUAUGGGCUUUGGGUCAUAAUGAUGUGUCAAUGUAGGCUUGAAUGUAACAAAUGUAACCACUCUGGUGGGGGAUGUCAUUCUAACAGGUAUGUAGUGGUAUCUUAUUGUGGUUGUAAUUUAAUUUAAUUACAUUUCCCUAUGACUAAUUGUGUUGACCAUCUUUCAUGUGCUCAUUUUCUAUCCAUAUAUCUUUUUUGGUGAAGUCUGUCCAGAUCUUUUGCCUGCUUUUUAAUCCAGGUUGUUUGUUUUCAUACCAUUGAAUUUCAAGUGUUCUUUGUAUAUUCUAGGUACAAAUUCAUUAUUAGAUAUUUGAUAUACAAGUAGUUUCCCCAGUCAAUGACUAGCCUUUGAAUUCGCUUACAGUGUCUUUUGCAGAGCAGAGGUUUUCAAUUUUGAUAAAGCCUAACUUAUCAUUUUUCCCUUAUGGAUUAUGCUGUUUGAUAACAUAUCUAAAUACUCAUCACCAAACCAAAGGUCAUGCAGAUUUUGCCCUAUAGAAAACGAAGUUUCUAGAAGUUUUCUAUUUUUGAUUUCAUUCUAUGAACAAUUUUGAGUUAAUUCUUGGGUAAGGUGUGAGGUUUAGGUUGAGAUUCUUUUUUUGUGUGCAUAUGAACAUACAAUCAUUCCAGCACCAUUUGUUAUAAACCAUUCUUUAUCUAUCAAAUUGCCUUUACACUUUUGUCAAAUAUCAGUUGAUUAUAUUUGUGUGUAUCUAUUUGUGGGCUCUCUAUUCUGUUCCACUGAUAUAUAUGUCUAUCCUUUACCGAUACCACACGGUCUUGAAUACUGUAGCUUUAUAGUCAAUGUUGAAAUUCCAUAAUGUGACUCCUCUGACUUUAUUAAUUUUUUUGCAGUUGUUUGGUUAUUCUAGUUCCUUUGCUUUUUGAUAUAAAUUUUAGAACCAAGUUACUGGGAUUUGGGGAGGGGAGGGACUAUGUUAAAUCUAUAGAUUAAAUUUGGGACAGUUGUCAUUUUAACAAUGUCGAGUCUUCCAUUCCAUGAAUAUAAUAUAUCUCUCCAUUUACUUAGCUCUUUAAUUUUAUUCAUUACAAACUGCAUUCCUGGGAUGAACCCCAUUUGGUUGUGACAUGUUUUGCCCUUUAUAUAUUACUAGAUUUGACUUGUGAAUAUUUUGUUCAGGAUUUUUGCAUCAAUAUUUAUGAGAGAUACCAGAGUGUAGUUUUCUUGUAAUUUCUUUGUCUGGUUUGGUAUUAGAUAAAUGCUGGCCUCAUAAAAUGAAUUAGGAAGCUUUCCCGUCUCUUCUACAUUCUCAAAAACAUUGUAUAGAAUUGGUGCUAUUUCUUCCUUAAAUAUUUGGUAGAAUUUGCCUGUAAAAUUUCCAGGGCCUGGAAUUUUCUUUCAGGAAGUUUUUAACUACAAAAUUAACUAUUUAAUAGAUAUAGAAAUUUUUCCAUUAUCUAUUUCUUUUUGAAUGAACUUUAUAAUUUCUGCCUUUUAAGAAAUUUGUCCAUUUUGUCCAAAUUUUAGAAUUUAUAAACAUAGAGUUGUUUGUACUGUUCCCUUAUUAUCCUUUUAAUGUCUGUGAUGUCUCCUCUUUCAUUCCUAAUAUUGGCAAUUUGUGUUUUCUGUGAUUUUUUCUUGGUCAGUUUAGCUAUAGGUUUACCAAUUUACUGAUUUUUCAAAGAAUCAGCAUUUAGUUUGUUUCUUCUCAUUUUCCUGUUUUCAAUUUUAUUGAUUCUUCCUCUAAUCUUUAUAUUUUUUUUCCUUCUACAUACUUUGGGUUUAAUUUGAUCAUUUUUCUAAUUUCCUGACAUGGGAGAUUAGAUCAUUGAUACGAGACUUUUAUUUUUCAAUGUAAGCAUUGAAGUCUGUACAUUUCCCAAUAGCUCCUGCAUUAGCAACUUCACACGAAUUUUAAUAUGUUGCAUUUUUAUUUUCAUUUUAUUCCAAAUGUAUUUUAAAUUUCCCCUAAAACAUCCUAAUUGACCCAUGCUUAUUUCAAAGUGUUUUUAUUUAAUUUCAGAAUAUUUGGAAGAUUUUCCCAAUCACUUUCUGUUACUCCUGUCUAGUUUAAUUCCCUUAUGGUUCAAGAAUAUGCUUUGUAUGAUUACUAUUGUUUAAAAAGCUUUUCUAUUCUUUUAAAUUUUUUUAAUGGCCUAUUCUUUUAAAUUUUUUAGUGGCCUAAAAUAUGACCUACCUUGGUGAAUGUUCUGUGCACCCUUGGAAGUGUAUUCUGCUAUUAUGUGGAGUGUUCUAUAAAUGUCAAUUAGGUCUAGUUGUUUGAUAGUGCUGUUUAGACCUUCUAUAUCUUAACUGAUUUUCUAUCUGCUUGAUCAAUUCCUGAAAGGGAAAUAUUAAAGUUUCUAACAAUAAUUAUGGAUUUGUCCAUUUCUCCCUUCAAUUUCACCAGUUUGUAAGAAAAUUUCCACUUUUUAGAUUCAGGGGGUACACAUGCAGGUUUGUGACAUGGGUACAUUUCAUGAUGCUGAGGUUUGGGAUAUGAAUGAUCCCGUCACCCAGAUAGUGAGCAUAGUACGCAGCAGGUAGUUUUACAAACCUCGCUACCCUCCCUCCACCCUCUAUUAGUCCCCAGUGUCUAUUGUUGCCAUCUUUAUGAGCAUAAGUACCCAAUGUUUAGCUCCCACUUAUAAGUGAGAACAUGCAGUACAUGGUUUUCUGAUCCUGUGUUAAUUCGCUUAGGAUAAUGGGCUCCAGCUGCAUCCAUGAUUUCAUUCUUUUUUAUGGCUAUGUAGCAUUUCAUGCUGUAUAUGGACCAAUUUUCUCCUUUUUUUUUCUUUUUUUUUUUUUGAGACGGAGUUUCGCCUUGUUGCCCAGGCUGGAGUGCAAUGGCACGAUCUCAGCUCACCACAGCCUCCGCCUCCCAGGUUCAAGUGAUUCUCCUGCCUCAGCCUCCCAAGUAGCUGGGAUUACAGGCAUGUGCCACCAUGCCCAGCUAAUUUUGUAGUUUUAGUAAAGACGGGGUUUCUCUGUGUUGGUCAGGCUGGUCUCGAACUCCUGAACUCAGGUGAUCCACCAGCCUCGGCCUCCCAAAGUGCUGGGAUUACAGGCGUGAGACACUGCGCCUGGCCAUAUUUGGACCAAUUUUCUUUACCCAGCCCACCGCUGAUGGGCACCUAGGUUGAAUCCAUGUUUUUACUAUUGUGAAUACUAAUGCAAUGAACAUAUGAGUGCAUGUGUCUUUUGAUAGAAUAACGUAUUUUCUUUUGGAUAUAUACCCAGUAAUGAGAUUGCUGGGUCAAAUGAUAGCUCUAUUUUAUGUUCUUUGAGAAAUUGCCAAACCACUUUCCACAGUGGCUGAACUAAUUUACAUUCUCACCAACAGUGUAUAAGCAUUCCAUUUUCUCUACAGCCUGGUCAGCACCUGUUCUUCUUUGACUUUAAUGAUAGCCAUUCUGACUGGUAUGAGAUAAUAUCUCAUGGUUUUGAUUUGCACUUCUCUGAUGAUUAGUGAUGUUGAGCAUUUUUUCAUGUCUGUUGGCUGCUUAUAUGUCUUCUUUUUAGAAGUGUCUGUUUAUGUGUUUUGCCCACUUUUUAAUGGUAUUAUUUGGUUUUUGCUUAUUGAAUUAAGUUCCUUAUAGAUUCUGAAUACUAGACCUUUGUCAGAUACAUAGUUUGCAAAUAUUCUCUUUCUUUUCUUUCUUUUCCUUCUCUCUCCCCACCCCUCCCCCACCCUCCUUUUUUGAGACAGUCUUAUUCUGUCGCCCAGGCUGGAAGGCAGUGGCGUGAUCUCAGUUCACUGCAACCUUGACCUCCUGGGCCUAAGCAAUCUUCCCACCCCAGCCUCCCGAGUAGCUGGAGCUACAGGCAUGUGCCACCACACCUGGCUAAUUUUUAAAUUUCUGUAGAGACAGGUUCUCUCUAUGUUGCCCAAGUGUCUCAAACUCCUGAGCUCAAGGGAUCCUUCCACCUCCGCCUCCCAAAGUUCUGGGAUUACAGGCGUGAGUCACUGCACCCGGCAGUUUACAAAUAUUUUCUCCCAUUCUGUAGGUUGUCUGUUUACUCUUUUGAUAGUUUCUUUCGCUGUGCAGAAACUGUUUAGUUUAAUUAGGUUCCACUUGUCAAUUUUCGUUUUUGUUGCAGUUGUUUUUCAGGACUUAGUCAUAAAUUCUUUCCCAAGGCCAAUAUUUAGAAUGGUGUUUCCUAGGUUUUCUUCUAGGAUUCUUAUACUUUGAGAUCUUUACAUUUAAAUCUUUAAUCUAUCUUGAGUUAAUUUUUGUUUAUGGUGAAAGGUAGGGGUGCAGUUUCAUUCUUCUGCAUAUGGCUAGCCAGCUAUCCUAGCACUAUUUAUUUAUUUAUUUAUUUAUUUUAUUAUACUUUAAGUUUUAGGGUACAUGUGCAAAACGUGCAGGUUUGUUACAUAUGUAUACGUGUGCCAUGUUGGUGUGCUGCACCCACUAACUCAUCAUUUACAUUAGAUAUAUCUCCUAAUGCUAUCCCUCCCCACUCCCCCACCCCAGCACUAUUUAUUGAAGAGGGAGUCCUUUUCCCAUACUUAUUUUUGCUGACUUUUUUGAAGAUCAUAUGGCUGUAGGUAUGCAGCUUUAUUUCUGGGUUCUGUAUUCUGUUCCAUUGGUCUAUGUGUCUGUUCUUAUGCCAAUAUCAUGCUGUUUUGAUUACUGUAGCCUUAGAGUUUCAAGUCAGGUAAUGUGAUGCCUCCAGCUUUGUUCUUUUUGCUUAGGAUUGCUUUGGCUAUUUGGGCUCUUUUUUGGUUCCAUGUGAAUUUAAGAAUAGCUUUUUUUCUAAUUCUGUGAAAAAAAUGAUGUUGGUAGUUUGAGAGGAAUAGCAUUCAAUCUGUAUAUUGCUGUGGGCAGUAUGGUCAUUUUAGUGUUGUUGAUUCUUCCAAUUCAUGAGCAUGGAAUGUUUGUCCAUUUCUUUGUUUCAUCUAUAGUUUUUUCAGCAAUGUUUUGAGUUCUUCUUGUAGAGAUCUUUCACCUCUUUGGUUAGGUGUAUUCCUAGGUUUCUUGUGCUUGUGUGUGGCUAUUAUAAAUGGGAUUGUGUAUUUAAA